CAGUUGCAGUAUUCUGCGGAAACCCUGAACAAGAGCGGUCGUCUGUUCCCUUUGGAGCUCAACGACCAGAGUCCCUGGAAGGUCUUCAGUGGAGGACCGCCCGUCAGAAGCCAGGCAGCCACGGGCCCUGAUUUCUCCUUCCUGCCGGGCCUGUCUGCUGCCGCUCACACCAUGGGUCUUCAGUGGCAGCCACAGUCCCCGCGCCCAGGCGCAGGCCUGGGUGCAGCCAGCACCGUGGACCCCAGUGAAAGCACAGGCUCGUCCACGGCCCCACCGACCAAGCGGCAUUGCCGGUCCUUGUCAGAACCCGAGGAGCUUGUGCGCUGCCGGUCCCCCUGGCGCCCCGGCAGCUCCAAGGUCUGGACUCCAGUCUCCAAGAGGCGGUGCGACAGCGGCGGGAGUGCCACGCGGCAGGGAAGCCCCGGCGCCGUCCUGCCGAGGAGUGCUGUGUGGUCGACCGGUCCCACCUCGCCCGCCACGCCCCGGCCGUCCUCCGCCAGCGGCGGCUUCGUGGACAGCAGCGAGGGCAGUGCGGGCUCAGGCCCGCUCUGGUGUUCCGCGGAGUCCUGCUUGCCCUCCACGAGGCGCCGCCCGUCCCUCUCACAGGAGCGACUCGCGGGUGCGGGCACUCCCCUGCCCUGGGCCAGCAGCAGCCCCACGUCCACGCCUGCGCUGGGCGGGCGCCGUGGGCUGCUCCGGUGCCGCUCACAGCCUUGCGUGCUCAGUGGGAAGAGGAGCCGGCGCAAACGGAGGCGUGAGGAGGACGCCAGGUGGACACGCCCAUCCUUGGACUUCCUGAAAAUGACCCAGCCGCACAGCUGUGCCCGCGAGUGCGAGUCCCGCGUCCGAGGCCUCGGCGUGAGCUUACAGCAUCUGUCGGGUCCGAGCAGUCAGUCCAGAGGGUCGACUCUGAAUGAAAACAAAACGCCGUGGUUUGAAAUGGAAGGAAACCUGGCCCCUGAAGACUUUAAAAAAUUCAAAAAGCCUUUGCUCCCUCAAUUACGAAGAUGACGAUGAGGAUGACACCCCAGUGAAGACGGUUCUGUCCUCCCCAUGUGACUCCCGGGGCCUCCCUGGCAUCACCAUGCCUGGCUGCAGCCAGAGGGGCCUCAGGACCAGCCCUGUCCACCCCAACCUGUGGGCCUCUAGGGAGUCGGUGACCAGUGAUGGCUCCCGCAGGAGCAGCGGGGACCCCCGUGAUGGGGACAGUGUCGGGGAGGAGGGCGUCUUCCCCCGGGCCCGCUGGGAGCUGGACCUGGAGCAGAUCGAGAACAACUGAGGCUGGUGGGGGCUGGUCGGGGCCAUGGCUGCCGCCUGCACCUGCCCUGGGGCACAGAGUAGGUUUCCUGUGAGCUGGUCGGGGCCACGGCCCGGCACCUGCCCUGGGGCACAGAGUAGGUUUCCUGUGAGCUGGUCGGGGCCACGGCUGCCGCCGGCACCUGCCCUGGGGCACAGAGUAGGUUUCCUGUGAGCUGGUCGGGGCCACGGCUGCCGCCGGCACCUGCCCUGGGGCACAGAGUAGGUUUCCUGUGAGCUGGUCGGGGCCACGGCUGCCACCGGCACCUGCCCUGGGGCACAGAGUAGGUUUCCUGUGAGCUGGUCGGGGCCACGGCUGCCGCCUGCACUGCCCUGGGGCACAGACUAGGUUUCCUGUGAGCUGGUCGGGGCCAUGGCUGCUGCCUGCACCUGCCCCAGGGCACAGAGUAGGUUUCCUGUGAGCUGGUCGGGGCCAUGGCUGCCGCCUGCACCUGCCCCGGGGCACAGAGUAGGUUUCCUGUGAGCUGGUCGGGGCCAUGGCUGCCACCGGCACCUGCCCUGGGGCACAGAGUAGGUUUCCUGUGAGUUGGUCGGGGCCACGGCUGCCGCCUGCACUGCCCUGGGGCACAGACUAGGUUUCAUGUGAGCUGGUCGGGGCCAUGGCUGCUGCCGGCACCUGCCCUGGGGCACAGAGUAGGUUUCGUGUUGCUUGGAACAUUAAGGCGUAAUUUUGAUUCAGUUUUUCCUAAAGAAGCAUUUUGCAUUUUUAUGGCUUUUGCAGUUCGGGAGAAAGCUUCUCUAUUUUGGAUGCAUUUCAGAAGGGCGUUCUAUUAAACAUGAAUCUGCAAACAGAUUAACAUGCGUCUGUGUUCCCCACGAAAGGCCUGCUGUGCAGGGCGCCUUGUGUGCUUUAGUUGCUAGGAAACCCCGGGCGUUGGUGGUCAGAGUCCCACUGGCCCCGUGUGUCCCCCCCUCCCGACGGGUCACGGUGCUUGGGGCUUGCGCAUGGGCAUCUGUGCCCAUGAACCUUGUCACCCACGUGCCAGUGAACCGCCAGCUUGUGGCCGCCUGGUUUUCCACCGGUGGCAGUGAUGGCCUUUGGGGCAGACCAAGGUGCCAUGAGUCCCUGCUUCCCGUGGCCUGGGAGGGCCCUUGCACCUUCAGGUGGGGUGUAGUGCCAGACCUCUGGGAAGGCUGUCCUGCCGGCAGCACCCGUCAGCACCCACUCUGUGAAUUUAAUACAAGGCCUUUGCUUUGUGCAUACGACUUCUGAUUAAUUUUCGUUUCCACCAUCUGAAGUGGGCCUGGCUGCGCCUCAGGCCUCUGGUCUCUGGCUCAGAACCAGACAAGGCAAGGGAUUUCCUGUUUUUCAUUCUUGCACUUUUAAUAAAAUCGUAGGGGUUUCGAGUUUGCGAUAGCAAAAGAAAACAUUAA